GCAGAGUCCCCGCAGCGCCGGUCGGGAGCGCAGCGCGGCGCACGUCGGCGCGCACGGCGGGACGGGCGCCGGAGUGGUCGGGCCUGGCGGCUGGACGGGCGCCCCUCGCUGCCCCGCGCGCUCCCCGCCGCCCCCCAUGAGCGCAGCCCCGCGCGGCCCGGGUCCGUAGGCGGCGGGGCGCCCCCCAUGCUGCUGCAGCCCGCGCCGUGCGCCCCGAGCGCGGGCUUCCCGCGGCCCCUGGCCGCCCCCGGCGCCAUGCACGGCUCGCAGAAGGACACCACGUUCACCAAGAUCUUCGUGGGCGGCCUGCCGUACCACACUACCGACGCCUCGCUCAGGAAGUACUUCGAGGGCUUCGGCGACAUCGAGGAGGCCGUGGUCAUCACCGACCGCCAGACGGGCAAGUCCCGCGGCUACGGCUUCGGGAUUAUUUUUGUCCUUGAAGGCCACAUUUCCCAGGCCUUGAACUUUGACGGGAGGAGCUGGAAUCCAGGAGGCAUCUUUGUGGGAGAGCCCCAGGUGACCAUGGCCGACCGGGCGGCAGCUGAGAGGGCUUGCAAAGACCCGAACCCCAUCAUCGACGGCCGCAAGGCCAACGUGAACCUGGCAUAUCUGGGCGCCAAGCCGCGGAGCCUCCAGACGGGCUUUGCCAUUGGGGUGCAGCAGCUGCACCCCACCUUGAUCCAGCGGACUUACGGCAGAAAAAUGGAAGUUUUCACAGAGGCCACAACAGGCUUCCACUUAAGUCUCACUGGCCACAACUGGGUGACAGGACACGGCCACCACAGGGGCUCUGAGAUGAGAAGACAGGCUCCUCGGACUCCGGAGUGUCAGGCUGACCCCGCACUACAUCUACCCACCAGCCAUCGUGCAGCCCAGCGUGGUGAUCCCAGCCGCCCCUGUCCCGUCGCUGUCCUCGCCCUACAUUGAGUACACGCCGGCCAGCCCGGCCUACGCCCAGUACCCACCGGCCACCUAUGACCAGUACCCAUACGCCGCCUCGCCUGCCACGGCUGCCAGCUUCGUGGGCUACAGCUACCCUGCCGCCGUGCCCCAGGCCCUCUCAGCCGCAGCACCCGCGGGCACCACUUUCGUGCAGUACCAGGCGCCGCAGCUGCAGCCUGACAGGAUGCAGUGAGGGGCGUUCCUGCCCCGAGGACUGUGGCAUUGUCACCUUCACAGCAGACAGAGCUGCCAGGCCAUGAUGGGCUGGCGACAGCCCGGCUGAGCUUCAGUGAGGUGCCACCAGCACCCGUGCCUCCGAAGACCGCUCGGGCAUUCCGCCUGCGCCCUGGGACAGCGGAGAGACGGCUUCUCUUUAAUCUAGGUCCCAUUGUGUCUUGAGGGAGGACUUUAAGAAUGACUGAGAACUAUUUAAAGACGCAAUCCCAGGUUCCUUGCACACCAUGGCAGCCUCUCCUUGCACCUUCUCCUGCCUCUCCACACUCCAGGUUCCCUCAGGCUUGUGUCCCCACUGCUGCAUCGUGGCGGGGUGUCACAGACCCUCUGCAGCCCCUGGCUGCCCUGGACUGUGCAGAGAUGCCUGACUCCAGGGAAACCUGAAAGCAAGAAGUUAAUGGACUGUUUAUUGUAACUUGAUCCUCCCGAGCUGUGAGCGCAGUCUGAGGUGUGAGGACACGGCCUCCUGUUGGAGUCCCAUUUUCUCCAUCAGGGCACGUGGGCGGCUUCCUCAAGCCCGGAGGAGCUCCCAGGCGCACAGGGGCCGCCGGUAACAGGGGCCGCCGGCCAAAGGCCCCUUUCCAGUCAUAGCACUGAAGUUGCAACUUUUUUCUUGUAAUUGUUUUGCUACUAAGAUAAUUUCAGAAGUUCAGUCUAUUUUUUCAGCGGAUACUGCCGCCACCAAGAAUCCAAAACCUAUUUUUGACUUGGAGAGACUUGCUUUUGUUGGUUCCGCCCGUGGAGACGACGAUAGUGUUUCUGUAUAAUAAAGUGUCUGCCGGCUCGCGGGCCAGGAUCCUCUCGGUGGGAUGGGCACCACAGACAGGAGGCCCCUCAGGCCCGUGCGGGCCACUGUCUGCUGCCGCCUGCCGGGGUGGCAGAGUGAGUUGUCUCAGGACCCCGUCACUGCGACGUUGACACUCCUCUCCCUUCCCUUCCUCCCCAACUCCCCAAACACUGUGGAAGGGGAGAAGGAAGUGAUCCACAGCAUUCAGGCCACUUGGGGUCUAGACCAUGGUGGUGCCAGCCUGGGGGGGGCAGUGGCCCUCAGCUCUGCCCGCUGGAGCGGUUGAGUGCAGAAGGGUGCGCCUCUUCCCUCUACCCCCGCACCACCUGCUGUGUGCCAGCCUGAGACGGUUCCUGCCUGUCUUGGGGGUUGGUGGAGGGUGGAGGCAGUUCUGCCAGCCGUGGCAGGGCUGCUAUGGGGCAUCCAGGGCUGUGGGGGUCUGGAGGAGGGGACAUGAGGUGAGAGGUAUCCUGGCCGAGGGCGGGGGGCAGCGGGGGGUCUCCCUCCGGACCUACCUCAGGGAGCUGAGCGUGCAGGCGCUCCAGGGCAGGCCUGGGACAGAGUCAAGGCUCAGAGAAUAAAGGUAGCUAAUCUCAUCAUAAUAUUUUUAUUAGAAUGUUCUGAUGAUAAAAAUAAAACUUGUUUUCUUUAAAGAAAAA